AGGAGCCCAGCUGGCUUCACCCAGUGGAUCACGCACUAGGGCUACAGGUGGAGCUGCUUGCCAGUCCGCCGCCGUGAGCCCACACUCCUCAGCCCUUGGGUGGUUGAUGGGACUGGGCGCUGUGGAGCAGCGGGCGGCGCUCGUCGCGGAGGCUCGGGCAUGGCGGGCUGCAGGUCCCUAGCCCUGCCCUGCAGGAAGACAGCUAAGGCCAGGCGAGAAAUUGAGCACGGCAGCUGCUGGCCCAGGUGCUAAGCCCCUCAACUGCCCGGGGCCGGUGGGGCCGGCAGGCGGCUCCGAGUUGCGAGGUCCGCGGGGCCCACGCCCACCCGGAACUCACGCUGGCCCGCAAGCACCGCGCGCAGCCCCGGUUCCUGCCCGCACCUCUCCCUCCACACCUCCCCGCAAGCUGAGGGAGCCGGCUCCGGCCUCGGCCAGCCCAGGAAGGCGCUCCCACAGCGCAGUGGUGGGCUGAAGGGCUCCUCAAGUGCCGCCAAAGUGGGAGCCCAGGCAGAGGAGGCGCCGAGAGCGAGGGAGGGCUGUGAGGACUGCCAGCACGCUGUCACCUCUCAAUAGCAGCCCAAACAGAUUAAGACAUGGGAGGUAUGGUCUCUAUUCUUACCAUCCAGACGUAUGUGAAGUAAAACCAGAGAACAACACAAAGCAAUCAAGAGGGUUUUUGCGCAGAGUUUGCAAAACGCCAAGGAGACUGUAGGUUUCUGUUAUAGUGAUUCAAAAGCCUGGGAUCCUCAUGUUAGGUGCUGCCUGAAAACAUGGCCUCCAGCCUCCAGGAGAGCUAAAAGCCGUGAGGAUUGGGGGUUGGGGAUGUCUGAGCCAUCUUAGGAUUCUGAUAAGGACUCAGUUCACUAUUUGUUUCUAGUUACUUUGUUUCUGUUUUUUUCAUUUUUUGUUUGUGUUAAAGUUUUAACCCCUGUACGUCAGAAUUGUUUAAUGUUUUUGGCUUGUCUAUGUGUUUUGAUUUUUUUUGUAUUAUUAUUUAAUUUUCCCAAUUCCCAUUAAAUCCUUAACCUCCUGACUUUUCUUUUUCUGCCUCCAUUUGUAUUGUUUAUUUCAUGUUACUAUAUCAUCUUAUGUUUCAGUAUUUUUCUGUUGAAUUUUAAUUCUUUUGUUUGGCUUUGGAGUCUGACUCAUUUUGUGUUGGCUCAUUAUUUUGCUUCAGGAUAUUUUUGUUGUUGUUAAAAUCUUUUAAUAUUCCUUUAUAAAUUUAAAUUUUUUUCUCUUUUAAUCGAAUUUAUUUGGGCUUAAGAGGGCACAAUAAUUUAUACCCUUAUUCACUUUCUGAGUUUGGAAACAACCAAGAAAAUAGAGGGGUCAGGAGGCUGGAAUUCAGAGUCUCGCUGGACUACAGAGAACGUGGCUUAGGGUGAAAGCACAGGCAUGCUGGGCAUCAUUGCUGCUUUGCACUGAUCAGAGAAGGAGAGACUUUAAAUGGGUUAACUCCAUGCAAUCAAGAAAGGUAGCCCCAUGUCAAUCCCUUACCAGUGAGGUAACUUCCAAUGUGGGUCAGAAGGAGUGGAUUGAGAGGCCGAGAACUGGGGGUAACCAAAAGAGUAAGACUAAACAAUACUCUCCUCUCAAUAUAAUUGUUACUUUUGUUCAUCUCCCUGUAAACCUCCCUCCCACUCUUCUGCCUUUUAUCUAUGGAGUGGGGAUGAGGUUGAGGGGAGACUCGGCCUACGACUACCAUGUUGGUCCCACAGCUCCACUUAGUUUCUGUCAAGCACACAUGAGACAAGGCAUGGCUAAGGUAAAGUCCUGACUGAUUCGACUGGUAAAGAUGCAAGGACACUUUUUUAGAAUCAGACCGUUUAUUCAUUACAUAGAUGACAAAAGGAAGACUAGCCAAAUGUGCCAACUCCUUGAGGUCAUUGUUCUGCUCAUCAAAAAGAAUGACACUGAAACCAAAGGGACUUGGAGAUUGCAAUGCGAGUUGGGUAAUGCAGCUCGGUGGUUUUGUGUUCUGCCACUCUAUUAAGAGAGGGUGAAGCAGGAAGACCCACGUCUCAUCAGAACACUGGAGGUGAUGAGAAACUGCUUCAUGACAGCUUCCCAGAUGUACAAGGGCAGCCGUGGGGCUGGCAACAGCUUCGUAAUCCUGGCUUCCUGCUUUCUGGGUCAAAGCCCUGGUGGUGUGUUCUUGAUAUCGGUCCAUCUAGUGGCGUUGUUUGAUUCCUCCCACCUUGCUGAUCAUUCGUAGUGUAGCCCCCAAGGUGUGGAAUAACCCUUAAGCCCUUACCGGGGUCCUUCUGGACUGAGAAUUGUUGUAAAGUAAUACUGCUCAGGUGAAAGACAACUUGAGUGGUUAAAUUACUGUCAUGCAAAGCGACUAGAUGGUUCAGCUGAUUGCACCUUUAGAAGUUAUGUGGAACGAGGCAGCAGAUCUUAAGUAUUUCAGUUUUAUGCUCUGCAACAAGUUUGGCCAUGUUGGAGGACAAUCCAAAGGUCAGCAAGUUGGCUACUGGCGAUUGGAUGCUCACUCUGAAGCCAAAGUCUAUUACUGUGCCCGUGGAAAUCCCCAGCUCCCCUCUGGAUGAUACACCCCCUGAAGACUCCAUUCCUUUGGUCUUUCCAGAAUUAGACCAGCAGCUACAGCCCCUGCCGCCUUGUCAUGACUCCGAGGAAUCCAUGGAGGUGUUCAAACAGCACUGCCAAAUAGCAGAAGAAUACCAUGAGGUCAAAAAGGAAAUCACCCUGCUUGAGCAAAGGAAGAAGGAGCUCAUUGCCAAGUUAGAUCAGGCAGAAAAGGAGAAGGUGGAUGCUGCUGAGCUGGUUCGGGAAUUCGAGGCUCUGACGGAGGAGAAUCGGACGUUGAGGUUGGCCCAGUCUCAAUGUGUGGAACAACUGGAGAAACUUCGAAUACAGUAUCAGAAGAGGCAGGGCUCGUCCUAACUUUAAAUUUUUCAGUGUGAGCAUACGAGGCUGAUGACUGCCCUGUGCUGGCCAAAAGAUUUUUAUUUUAAAUGAAUAGUGAGUCAGAUCUAUUGCUUCUCUGUAUUACCCACAUGACAACUGUCUAUAAUGAGUUUACUGCUUGCCAGCUUCUAGCUUGAGAGAAGGGAUAUUUUAAAUGAGAUCAUUAACGUGAAACUAUUACUAGUAUAUGUUUUUGGAGAUCAGAAUUCUUUUCCAAAGAUAUAUGUUUUUUUCUUUUUUAGGAAGAUAUGAUCAUGCUGUACAACAGGGUAGAAAAUGAUAAAAAUAGACUAUUGACUGACCCAGCUAAGAAUCGUGGGCUGAGCAGAGUUAAACCAUGGGACAAACCCAUAACAUGUUCACCAUAGUUUCACGUAUGUGUAUUUUUAAAUUUCAUGCCUUUAAUAUUUCAAAUAUGCUCAAAUUUAAACUGUCAGAAACUUCUGUGCAUGUAUUUAUAUUUGCCAGAGUAUAAACUUUUAUACUCUGAUUUUUAUCCUUCAAUGAUUGAUUAUACUAAGAAUAAAUGGUCACAUAUCCUAAAAGCUUCUUCAUGAAAUUAUUAGCAGAAACCAUGUUUGUAACCAAAGCACAUUUGCCAAUGCUAACUGGCUGUUGUAAUAAUAAACAGAUAAGGCUGCAUUUGCUUCAUGCCAUGUGACCUCACAGUAAACAUCUCUGCCUUUGCCUGUGUGUGUUCUGGGGGAGGGGGGACAUGGAAAAAUAUUGUUUGGACAUUACUUGGGUGAGUGCCCAUGAAAACAUCAGUGAACUUGUAACUAUUGUUUUGUUUUGGAUUUAAGGAGAUGUUUUAGAUCAGUAACAGCUAAUAGGAAUAUGCGAGUAAAUUCAGAAUUGAAACAAUUUCUCCUUGUUCUACCUAUCACCACAUUUUCUCAAAUUGAACUCUUUGUUAUAUGUCCAUUUCUAUUCAUGUAACUUCUUUUUCAUUAAACAUGGAUCAAAACUGA